UUCAGACAUGAUUAUGGAGCAGGCUUGUUUUGUCUUGCUCUGCCGCGGUCACAGAGUGGCCUUGUCUGAUGUCGGCGUCAUGUGAGAUUGUUUAUGUCCAGCAGGAGGACACCAGGGCCCUGCUUUGACUGCCAGGCCAGCUCCUAGCAACACCAAGGCCAGCUGUGAACACCAGGCCAGCUCCUGUGUCUUUUUCAAAGUUCUUAGCUGUGAUGGAUCCUUGCAAUGAAAGAAUUAAGAAGGGCGGGUGCGGUGGUUCACGCCUGUAAUUCCAGCACUUUGGAAGGUCGACGUGGGAAGAUUGCUUAAGCCCAGGGCUCAAGGCCAGCCUGGGUAACAUGAACAAUUCUUAACGUCCAAAGAUAACGUCUUUCCUUAACGUCGAAAGAUGCCUUGUUGUGAUAUUACAGCAGUCAUUCCUGCUCACUACGGGCAGGCAGACAGUGCAGAAAAGGUGAAGCACAAAAACUAAAAAGGAAAAUCUCUCCUUGAACCACUGCGAACAGAUCCGAGUGCUGGGGUACUGCUGCCAGCUGGUUGGUGGAGUUCUGGUUGAACAGUGUCCCGCCAGGUCCGAAGUGGGGACACGUCUGUUGGUGGUGUCCACCCAACUCAGCCACUGCAGGACCAUCUUGCGACUCUUUGAUGACCUGGCCAUGUUUGUCUACACUAAGCAAUAUGGCCUGGGGGCACAGGAGGAGGACGCCUUUGUCCGCUGUGUCUCCGUCCUAGGGAACCUGGCUGACCAGCUCUACUACCCCUGUGAGCACGUGGCCUGGGCGGCUGAUGCCCGGGUCCUCCACGUGGACUCUUCUCGGUGGUGGACGCUGAGUACAACCCUGUGGGCCCUCUCUCUGCUCCUGGGGGUUGCCAGGUCCCUGUGGAUGCUGCUGAAACUGAGACAGAGGCUGCGGAGCCCCACGGCGCCCUUCACCAGCCCGCUGCCCCGGGGCAAGCGGAGGGCCAUGGAGGCGCAGAUGCAGUCGGAGGCGCUGUCACUUCUCAGCAACCUGGCCGACCUGGCCAACGCCGUGCACUGGCUGCCCCGGGGCGUGCUGUGGGCCGGCCGCUUCCCGCCGUGGCUAGUGGGCCUCAUGGGCACCAUCUCCUCAAUCCUCAGCAUGUACCAGGCGGCCCGGGCCGGCGGCCAGGCCGAGGCCACUACCCCCUGACACUGCCGGAAGAGCACAGGGACACAGCCAGAGCCCACGGAGGGCCCUUCCCGCAAAGCAGAAGCCGCCAGGGCAGGGGCCGGGGCUCUCAUGGAGCUGCCUGUGGUGAAACCCAUGGGCAGGGUGGGUGGAGGGACUGAUGCGAGGUCCCCCAGGCCUCAGCCUGGAGCUCCUGAGCCGUGACAGUUUUCAGGGGCCGUGCAGGGCUUCAGCAGCACCUCCUGCCUGCCAGCUGGCGUCUUGUAUCCAAAUCAAGAUGAGGAAGAGGGGGCCUGUCGUGCCUUGAGAAAGCUGGAACGGGAAUCAAUUAAACAUUGUGGUGCUGGC